GGGUGUGAGCCCCACGUGAGGCUUGGUAGGACUGCGGACGGUGAGUGGGGAUGGACUGGAGUUGAAGAGCUCGAGAUGAAGGGCUUGAGGGCGUGUGUGUGUGUGGCGCGGGGAAAAAACUAGUCUCUAACAGGAUCUCUUUCGGAUCUGCGAGGGGUUUUGCCCCUUCCUCCUGAGCCUUUUUCGGUCUCAUUCUUCAGUCUUCAUCGAUCCUUUUCAGGGUCGCUUCUCGAAUCAGUCUGUUAGCUGCCCCCCUGCGGUACAGGAGGUGGAAAGGAGACCCUAGUUCAGGGGCCAGCCCUGUGUUCUCCGAAUUAGAGAGCGGGCAGAAGGGGAGGGUGGGCUACGGGGAUGCGGGCGCGUGUCGGGAGUGAGGUCCGGUCGCCUUCCCCUCUCUCGGAUUAUCUGACAUAUAAUGAGUGCUUUCCUUCUAAACAUUUACAAUACAUGCAGUACUUCUCCUGGUUGAGGUGGUACCUACCUCGUAAGAUUGCUCAGAGAGUUAAGUGCUGUAAUACAUCGAAAAAUGUGUAAAUGCACCAGCGAUAGCUUCCUUUUUUUUCCUAGUUAGUGUAAUUAAAAGGACUUGAUUUUUAAAUAAGAAAUAUUGCCCUUUUAAUCAUUUUGGGGGGGGGUUGCUUAAUAAUCAACGACUUUUGGCUCUUUGCAAAAUUCCCAUCCAGAGAUGCUAAACCAUUGGAGACUUUUCACAAGGGAACAAUAUUAAUUUAUACACACAUAUGUAUAUGUUCUAGUAUGUUUUGGGGGAAUGAGCUCACUUGGGCCUUCAUCACUGGUAGAAUCAGAUAUUAUAGAAAGAAGUGAUAUUUAUUAACUGGUGUGAGACUUUACCUGGAGACUCAAAUUUACUUUUUAUUUUUAAACUUUUUAUUACUUUUGAAGGAUGAUCGAAUUUAAAAAGGAAACUUUCUUAGCUAAACCUGAGUUGAUUUUGGUCUGUUUAGUUAGAAUGCUAGUCUUACAGAACUAAAGGCUGUUUGUUGGCAGUAGCCGGAGAUAAGGAGUAAGCAGAAUGAGACCAGAAUGUGAAGAAACAAAUGAGGCCAACGGAGGCUAGGGAAUCUUUCUUUCUUACUUUUUUUUGGUAGACAGGGUCUCACUCUGUUGCCCCAGCUGGUGUGCUGUAGUGCCGUUAGGCUCACUCUAGCCAAGACCUCCCGGGUGGAAGUGAUCCUCUUGCCUUAGCCUCCAAAGUAGCUGGGACUACAGGCGCGCGCCACCAUGCCGGGCUCAUUUUUGUAUUUCUUGUGGGGAUUCACCAUGUUACCCAGGCUGGUCCUGAACUCCUGGGCUCAAGUGAUCCGCCCGCCUUGGCCUCCGAAAGUGCUGGUGAGCCACCGCACUCGGCCUAGGGAAUCUUAACUACAUUUGCCUUCAAUUAGUAACACAUACUGGUAUACAAAUAGAAAUUCUAAGUGAGAGCAAUGGAUGAAUAAACAUUUGUUCCCCUCCAUAAAGCCCUGGGAUUCUGCUUUGUCUACCUUAAGUUUAUUUCUCUAAAUGAUCUGUCAUGGAAAGAGGAUAUUUUGUAUUUGUUUUCUUCAAGCAUUUGGUCGAGAUUAAGAAUUAAAAAUGUCAUCCAAACAAGAAAUAAUGAGUGACCAGCGGUUUAGACGGGUUGCAAAGGACCCGAGAUUUUGGGAAAUGCCAGAAAAGGAUCGAAAAGUCAAAAUUGACAAGAGAUUUCGAGCCAUGUUUCAUGACAAGAAGUUCAAGUUGAACUAUGCCGUGGAUAAAAGAGGGCGCCCCAUUAGCCAUAGCACUACAGAGGAUUUGAAGCGUUUUUACGACCUUUCAGAUUCUGAUUCCAAUCUCUCUGGUGAAGAUAGCAAAGCAUUGAGUCAAAAGAAAAUAAAGAAGAAAAAAACCCAGACUAAAAAAGAAAUCGAUUCAAAAAAUCUAGUUGAGAAAAAGAAAGAAACCAAGAAGGCUAAUCACAAGGGUUCUGAAAAUAAAACUGAUUUAGAUAAUUCUAUAGGAAUUAAAAAAAUGAAAACCUCAUGUAAAUUUAAGAUAGAUUCAAACAUAAGUCCGAAGAAGGAUAGCAAAGAAUUUACACAAAAAAAUAAGAAAGAGAAAAAAAACAUUGUUCAACAUACUACAGACUCUUCUCUCGAAGAAAAACAAAGGACAUUAGACUCAGGCACCUCUGAAAUUGUGAAAUCUCCCAGAAUCGAGUGUUCUAAGACAAGAAGAGAAAUGCAAUCAGUGGUUCAACUCAUAAUGACAAGAGACAGUGAUGGUUAUGAAAACUCAACAGAUGGUGAAAUGUGUGACAAAGAUGCUCUGGAGGAAGAUUCAGAAAGCGUUAGUGAAAUAGGAAGUGAUGAGGAAUCUGAAAAUGAAAUUACAAGUGUUGGUAGAGCUUCAGGUGAUGACGAUGGAAGUGAAGAUGAUGAAGAGGAGGAUGAAGAUGAAGAGGAGGAUGAAGAUGAGGAUAGUGAGGAUGAUGAUAAAAGUGACAGUGGCCCUGAUCUUGCAAGGGGUAAAGGAAAUAUAGAAACUAGUUCUGAAGAUGAAGAUGAUACGGCAGAUUUGUUUCCAGAAGAAUCUGGUUUUGAGCAUGCUUGGAGAGAAUUAGAUAAAGAUGCUCCUCGUGCUGAUGAGAUUACACGUCGAUUAGCAGUUUGUAACAUGGACUGGGAUAGAUUAAAGGCAAAAGAUUUGCUGGCUCUGUUCAAUUCAUUUAAACCCAAAGGAGGUGUAAUAUUUUCCGUCAAGAUAUAUCCUUCAGAAUUUGGAAAGGAGAGGAUGAAGGAAGAGCAAGUUCAAGGACCAGUAGAGCUAUUAAGUAUUCCUGAAGAUGCCCCAGAAAAAGACUGGACGUCUAGAGAAAAAUUGAGAGAUUAUCAAUUCAAACGACUGAAGUACUAUUAUGCAGUAGUAGACUGUGAUUCUCCGGAAACAGCUAGUAAAAUUUAUGAGGAUUGUGAUGGCCUGGAAUUUGAAAGUAGUUGUUCUUUCAUAGAUCUAAGGUUUAUACCAGAUGAUAUUACUUUUGAUGAUGAGCCUAAGGAUGUAGCCUCAGAAGUGAAUUUAACAGCAUAUAAACCAAAAUAUUUCACUUCUGCUGCAAUGGGAACAUCAACGGUGGAAAUCACUUGGGAUGAGACUGAUCAUGAAAGAAUUACAAUGCUCAACAGGAAGUUUAAAAAGGAAGAGCUUUUGGACAUGGAUUUUCAAGCCUACUUAGCUUCCUCUAGUGAAGAUGAAGAGGAGAUAGAAGAGGAGCUACAAGGUGAUGAUGGAGUCAAUGUAGAAGAAGAUGGGAAAACAAAGAAAAGUCAGAAGGAUGAUGAAGAACAAAUUGCUAAAUACAGGCAGCUCUUGCAGGUUAUUCAAGAAAAAGAAAAGAAAGGCAAAGAAAAUGAUAUGGAAAUGGAAAUUAAAUGGGUUCCAGGUCUUAAAGAAAGUGCAGAAGAGAUGGUCAAAAACAAAUUGGAAGGAAAGGAUAAACUGACCCCUUGGGAACAAUUUUUAGAGAAGAAGAAAGAGAAAAAAAGACUGAAAAGGAAACAGAAGGCUCUUGCUGAAGAGGCCAGUGAAGAGGAACUUCCCUCUGAUGUUGAUUUGAAUGACCCAUACUUUGCUGAAGAAGUUAAACAAAUAGGUAUAAAUAAAAAAUCGGUAAAAUCUGCAAAAGAUGGCACAUCUCCAGAAGAAGAAAUUGAAAUAGAAAGACAAAAGGCUGAAAUGGCUUUGCUUAUGAUGGAUGAGGACGAGGACAGUAAGAAACACUUCAAUUACAACAAGAUUGUGGAGCACCAGAAUCUGAGCAAAAAGAAGAAAAAGCAGCUCAUGAAAAAGAAGGAAUUAAUAGAGGAUGACUUUGAGGUAAAUGUUAACGAUGCACGGUUUCAGGCAAUGUACACUUCCCACUUGUUCAAUUUGGACCCCUCAGAUCCCAAUUUCAAGAAAACAAAAGCUAUGGAAAAAAUCCUUGAGGAGAAGGCCCGGCAAAGAGAACGGAAAGAACAAGAACUUACUCAGGCAAUAAAGAAAAAAGAGAGUGAGAUUGAAAAGGAAUCACAAAGGAAGUCCAUUGAUCCUGCUUUGUCAAUGUUGAUUAAAUCUAUAAAAACCAAAACAGAGCAGUUUCAAGCAAGAAAAAAGCAAAAAGUCAAAUAACUGGAUGUUACUUAUUUUUGAACUGAAUACAUCUUUUCCUAAAAUGUACAAAAAUAAUAGGAGGGAAUAUUUAUUGGGAACAAAGCUAUCUUUCAAGAACAUGAAUAAAAUCUUUUUCUGGACAUAGUAAAAUUUUUCUCCAUAAAUAAUUGUACUUAAUUGUGGAUGACUGACAAAUUUUUAUUGUAUAUUCCUACAGAUCAGUCAUAAUUAAAUUACCUGCAUUAUAGGGUUUAUAAAAUUUUUAUAUUUUACAAUGUUCAGUUCUAACUAGUGGAAAGUUACUCUAGCUUUUUAAAAGGCUGUUUACAAUUCUGUGUAAAAAUAGAGCAGUAUCUACUCAAGUUUGUGUAAAUGUUAGGGAUAAUUUGAAAAAUAUAUAUAUUUAAUACAUUAAUUUCUCUGGAAGCAGGAGGCAUGUUUAAAUAACUAUUAAAAUAAUUUAUUUUUCUAGCCAUAAAGGAUGGAAGUCAAGAACUUUUUGUUGUUUAGUCAUGUUAAGUAUAGUUUAUGAAAUUAACUUGUAAAUAAAAGUGUAAAAUAUUUUCA